AUGGCUGGAGGGCAGCCCAUUUCCAGGAGGUCCACAGCCCAGAUUGGCAGUCAUCAAUACCCUUUCCUGGCCACGCCAUUCUCCAAAUUGCUCACACAGCUGGCACUGUUGCCUCCUCAGCCCCGGCUGCCCCUCUCGUUUUAUGCUGCCAUCCAGUCUUCCCUCAGGCAAUUUAGAAUCUACUACACACAUUGCUAUUUGAACACUCACAGAAAACUAUUAUCUUCCCCCCGCCCUCUACAAAGCAUCUCCAGGGCUCAUAUUAUUGUGAGGCCUCUAUUUUCAUCCUUGCAACCAAUGUUCAGAGCUUACAGAGCUUAUCAUGUUUAUUAUAUAACAAUAAGACACAAGCCAAAACAACUUGCUGCUGGGCUUUUAAACAUAGCAACAGCAGAAAUCUUUUCUGGGCUUGAGGAAGAGCCACUUCAAAUGUCUACUAAUUUCAGCAAUUUUCUGGUCUAUGGAAUGAAAAGUCUAAAACUCACAGCCCUCUGCUCCACCAUCGGACUUCAUGACGCAAGGGGGCGGGUGGGGAAGAAAGUGGCGCGCUCCCUGGUUGUUGGGAUUCACAGGCUGCCUCUCAAAGGAGUAUUGCCUGGGUGGCGAAUGCUCUUGGAGGAGAAAAGAGAAAGGCAUGAAACGGGGACCCUUCAAAGUUGCCACCAUGGUAAUGUCACUCAGUGGCACAGGGCUUGUUCCUCCCUUUUGUUCUCUUUUCUUUUUUUU